AGCAGCAGCGGUAGAGCAGUGACCAGGCGUCUCCGCGAUGGGCCCCGGGGACUUCCGCCGCUGCAGAGAGAGAAUUUCCCAGGGGCUCCAGGGACUCCCAGGUAGAGCGGAGCUUUGGUUCCCACCUCGUCCCGCGUGCGACUUCUUCGGGGACGGCAGGAGCACGGACAUCCAGGAGGAGGCCCUCGCCGCCAGCCCGCUGCUGGAGGACCUCAGACGACGGCUGACGCGCGCCUUCCAGUGGGCGGUGCAGCGCGCGAUCUCGAGGCGCGUGCAGGAGGCGGCGGCGGCGGCGGCGGCGCGGGAGGAGCAGAGCUGGACGGGCGUUGAGGCCACCCUGGCCAGGCUGCGGGCGGAGCUGGUGGAAAUGCAUUUCCAAAACCACCAGCUGGCUAGAACUUUACUGGACCUAAACAUGAAAGUGCAGCAAUUGAAAAAGGAGUAUGAACUGGAAAUUACAUCAGACUCCCAAAGCCCAAAAGAUGAUGCUGCGAAUCCGGAAUAAAGAAAUGCACACGCAAGGGCUGGGCGCGGUGGCUCACGCCUGUAAUCCCAGCACUUUGGGAGGCCGAGGCGGGCGGAUCAAGACGUCAGGAGAUUGAGACCAUCCUGGCUAACACUGUGAAACCCUGCCUCUACUAAAAAUACAAAAAAUUAGCCAGACGUGGUGGCAGGCACCUGUAGUCCCUGCUACUCAGGAGUCUGAGGCAGGAGAAUGGCGUGAACCCAGGAGACAGAGCUUGCAGUGAGCCGAAAUCCUGCCACUGCACUCCAGCCUGGGUGACAGAGCAAGACUCCAUCUCAAAAAAAAAAAAAAAAAAAAAAGCACACGCGAAGCUCUGGAUCCUAAAACUAACGCAUACAACCCUGAAACAAUUCUGAUGAACACAUUAUGCUUUGCAUAAGUUUUGAGGGGCAAUUUAUAGACCCAAAACAAAUGACAGGGGAAGGUGACAGAAAAACAUCUAAGAGAGGGGAGAGAAAAAUGAUGUAUUACCAAGUUUUAAAGUUAUUUAUUUGUUAUUUUUACUGGGACAUAGAAGUAAAAUAUAACUAUAGAUAAAUCUCUCUCUGUCUCUCUCACUCAAAGAAUGCUUUAAUGCCAACUUUCGGUAUUCAACCUUGUGUCACCUGACCUUUCUGGCAUUGCCUGAGCUUUCAGAGUUUGUGCUUGUUUUGUUUUACUUGAUUAUUCUCAGUUUGUCUGUCCAGCAGCCUGCCCUGCUUCUUGUGGAGAAUUGUUUCUACUUGGAUUCUAACCAUGCCCUUUAGGUGGUCUGUGACUAAGGGUAUUCCAUCUUCCUGGAUAUAGUCAUGCAGCUCAAGGCAGGCAGAUGGGUUUGUCCUUAGGAUUUUUGAAUGGGCACUAAAAGAGUAGAUGACUAUUUCUGCCAGUAGAAGCUGUGGAUCAGGGGCUUGGAAGCUGCUGGUGGUCACCAUGUGAGAAAGCCCACACCCUAAUGGAGGUGACUGAAACGGAACCACUAAAAGCACAAAAGGGGAGGGAGGGAGGGAGGGUGCUUCGCUUCCUUGUUCCUGGGGUCAAGCUGUAUAAGACUCCAGGCCUUGCUCUUGUUUAUGUACAUGAAAUAUUCUGAUAUCCUUCUCAUAAAAUCUCUUUUUGCCUAAGUAAAUUCAAGCUGGAGUUUCAUGACUUGUAUCUAGUGUUCAUAACUAAUACAGUUGUUCAGUUUUAGGAGUUAAAAUGGUUCUUACUGUUGAAUUGGACUAUCUAACUGUACCCGAAAAGUGCUGUCUUUUUAAUGCAAACAGUAAAGUUAAUAAAAAAUAGUUGCAGAUCUAAGUGAUAUUUAUAAUGGUUAUUGUCUGCAAAAUACAAAUUAAUUUAUAACAAGCUAUGUAAUUUUAAUAUUUAAUAAACUAUAAAAAUCAGUUCUUGAAGACAAAGGAGAACAGAAGAGACACAGUCUUUCUCUUGUUAAAAGAAAUACAAGGACAAGCAUGGUGGAUCACGCUUGUAAUUCCAGCACUUUGGGAGGCUGAGGUGGGCAGAUUGUUUGAGCUCAGGAGUUUGAGACCAGCCUGGUCAACAUGGCAAAACCCCAUCUCUACUAAAAAUACAAAAAUUAGCCAGGCGUGGUGGUGCUCGCCUAUAGUACCAGCUACUCAGGAGGCUGAGGCAUAAGAAUCACUUGAACCUGGGAGAUGGAGGUUGCAGUGAGCCGAGAUCAUGCCCCUGCACUCCAGCCUGGGUGACAGAGGGGGACUUGGCCUCGAAAAAAUAAAUAAAUAAUAAAAAUAAAAUAAAUGCAAGUUGUUUUAUGUGUGUG